ACUUCCUGUUCCUCCAUCUCCAGCGGACACUGCUCUUUCAAGGGCAGGUCUCCAGCCCAGCUCUCUGAAAACAUUUUGCUGAAAAUAUAAGCAAACAUCGGCCUUGUCCUCCUUGUGUUCAUACACUGUGGAAGCUUUUCUCUGCCUCCUCCGUGAGAGUGCGUGGCCGGGAGACCAGAAACGUGGUCCUUUCUCUUGCCUGUGAGCUGGUGCAGAGAUGGAGGAAGAAGAAUAUGAACAAAUUCCCCAGGAGAAUCCCCCAGAAGAGCUGUCCCAGGAUCCUGUGCUGGAGCUGUCAGGAGGCUCUGCUCUUGCACUGGGAGAGAACGUUCAGCCCCACCUUCAAGGAUGUGGGCCCAGAAUGGUGGCCCAGCGCUGGUUUCAGGGCAGAUGUUGGUCUUUUACAAUCUGCCCCUGCAGUCUGGGGGUACACCCAGAGGCUCCUGGUGAUGACAAGAUGGGGUACAUGGGCCCUUACCCCAGUUCCCUCUGCUUUCUUUGGAUAUUUCUAGGUCUAAGGGAGAAAGAACAGAAGACCCCAAGGAGACUGAGGCUCAUUCUCAUGGGGAAAACAGGGAGUGGGAAGAGUGCAACAGGAAACAGCAUCCUCGGCAGGGACGUCUUCGAGUCUAAACUCAGCACCAGACCCGUGACCAAGACCUCCCAGAGACGGAGCCGAGAGUGGGCUGGGAAGGAGCUUGAGGUGAUUGACACACCCAACAUUCUGUCCCCCCAGGUCUCGCCAGAGGUGGCAGACGCUAUCUGCCAAGCCAUCGUCUUAUCCGCCCCAGGGCCCCACGCCGUGCUCCUGGUGACACAACUGGGCCGGUUCACGGAUGAGGAUCAGCAGGUGGUCAGGCGCCUGCAGGAGGUCUUUGGAGUGGGGGUUCUGGGUCACACCAUCCUGGUGUUCACCCGGAAGGAAGACCUGGCUGGCGGCUCCCUGGAAGACUAUGUGCGAGAGACCAACAACCAGGCCCUUGCCUGGCUGGAUGUGACCCUUGCACGGCGCCAUUGCGGCUUCAACAACAGGGCACAGGGGGAGGAGCAGGAGGCCCAACUGCGAGAGCUCAUGGAGAAAGUUGAAGCCAUUAUGUGGGAAAACGAAGGAGAUUAUUACAGCAACAAGGCUUACCAAUAUACCCAGCAAAACUUUCGGCUGAAAGAACUACAGGAAAGGCAAGUAAGCCAGGGCCAAGGCUCUGAGGACGUGCCUGGUGAGGAGUCUUGGCUGGAAGGACUGUCCCAGAUCCAGAAGGAAUCUGAGGAAGCCCACAGAUGCCUGCUGGGGAAGGCUGACCUUUGAGCCUGUGCUGGACUUGAGCCAAGGACACCAUCAGCCUUUGCACCCCCCUGUGUCCAGCCCUCUGUUUCUCUUUCCAUCCCAUGGAGUGCUUCCCAGUCUCCAGGUCAUGACGUCUGGUGUAGGAAGAGGGGCAUGGGGCUUGAGGACAGGGUCCAGCAUGCCCAGAUCACAUUCCAGUUCCUUCAUUCCUUCUUCCAGAACAUCUGGGUCCUCCCUCCUCUGUGCCCCAACAGCACGCUGUCUUCCUAUUGGACCUUCUAUCUCAUUGCAUUGCCUUUCAUGAGUUACUUGUCUAUACUCUGAUAGAACCAAAGUUUCUUGAGGGCAGGCCUGUAUCUUUUACUUCUGUGUAACUUCCACAGCUUUUGACUGCAUUGGAGUCAUGCAGUCACGUUUGGUGCGGCAACUCCAUGCAAGCUGUUGACCAGAUGACUUCUCAUCUCUCCCCACACCAUGAUGGUUUAAGGUGCCUGUUGUGUCUGGUGGCUGGAACAUGGCAGUGGUGCUGAGACAUGGGGAGGGUUGGAGACUGGGUGGGGAGGGUUGGAGACUGGGCUGGGAGGAGAGCAAGCAGGAACAGGGAUGGAGGCAGGAGGAGCAGCCCUUUUAUUCACUCUUGAGCUGUAACAAACAAGCCCCGUUGGAACUUCCUAGUGGGAAUGAUGGGAGAAGUUUGGGGCAGGGUAUCCAAGAAGUCAGACUGUGGUCAAGUAGGUGGUCCCUUGCCCUGGCUACAGAACAUGGAAGCCCCUAGGGAUGCAAGUGGACUUGGGCAGAGGAGGUCACACCACCCCACCAAGGUAGACUUAGAUUAGAGAUGACUUGCAUCUGUUACUUCCCCUUUUUCCAUGGGUUUCAUGGCCCCUCAUGAUAUUUGCCUUCUGCUCCUAGAAGGCACAGACUACUUUCAACCUGCCUCGCCCUUCACUGCCACCCCUCCCUUCUCCCUUGAUAAUGGGAGCAUGUGGAUGGGGUGUCUGCGUGUGCAAACGGGUUCCCUAGCAAAGUAUUUGUGGGGGUCCAAUGCAAGGAGGCAGGGAAGAAAGGGGGCCUGCAAAGGAAGCAGUAGAGUGACUUAAACAUCUUGCGAGGCAGCCUGCCUGGUUUAUGGGAGAACUCUGAAGCCCAUGAUGUUUUCCUGGAAGGCUGUUCCUACAGACGGGGUUUAUAAGUACUGAUACUGGACAGGAUGAGAAGGGAGUAGGAUGUCAUCCUGUCUCAGGCCUCGGAUAGGAAGCUGCCUGCCAGCAAGAGGAGACUGAUGUGCCCCGGGUGCACCCCACCUCCUUUGAGGUCCAAGAUGCUCCUGGGGAGUUGACCGACAUUUGGGAAGAUAAUAGGAGGCAUUGGGGAAACUGCUCCCCAAUAUAUUCCUCUUUUCCUUUCUUCAAGCUGCGUAGCAGGGGGCCUUUAGCUAGUUUCUCCCGAGAGGGGCGGGAAGUACAGCUGGUGGAGACAGUGCUGGGAGAUGAUCAGAAAUCUCAGGGCACAGCCUCAGGUCUACCUGGACACUCAUCCACUGUUGGAGAUGCUCAACAGCUAGACACAGAUGCUCACAGCCGACCUGUGGCCUCUUGCUCUGAAGCCAUCCCCCAUCUUCCCUAGACACAGCAGACAUCUGAGAAAGCUUCAGCAUUUCUCUUGCUAACAGAUUCAGAAAAGUGUCUCAAAGCAGAGCACAGAGUUAUUUGGUGUUUGCUGAAGACAGCCUUUGUGCCACAAUCACUUAUUAAAUAAGCGAUCAAUUUCCCAUUGAACUGAACAUGCAACAUUUAUCAUACAUUCAGUUCUCAUUCACACUCCUUAAGAUUUGGUCAGAAUUUUUAUUUCUGUUCAUGUCUUCUACUUUUCUACUCCUGUAUGAAUAAAAUAUUGAUUUGAUUACAGUGGCUUUGACUAUAAUGUGGGAGCCAAUUUUUGCCUCAGUCUUCAUUUUUAUAUUUACCUUGUUAUUCUCAGGCAUUUUUUUCUUCUAUGUGAGAGUUAAAAUCAUUCUGUAAUUUCCCCCCAAAAUCAUAUUGGUAUUCUAGUUGGCAAUGUCUUACAUUUAUGUUAAGUUUGAGGGAAUUGGUAGUUCAAGUAUAAGUUAAUUAAGGCCAUUUUAUUUCUAAGUGAACAGACUUGAAACUCCAGAGCUACUGAAGUAAAAGUUAGAAUCAUUUGCAUUUUCAUUCAGAUAGGAGAUAAUUUUGUAAAUUUUGAUGCUAUUAUUUUAACUCUAUUAGCUUAAGUAAUGUCAUAAUAGAAAACACAAGCAUUUGACCAAAUGAGAUCCAUUCAGCGACUAACUGGCAAGGCACUCAAAACAUGUCAUUCAUUAAAUGUUGUUUUUAUUUACCUCAAA